GCAAUCGGUUCCAAACAGCAGUUAGGUCAGCAGUCCGCUCAGCCGAGGCAGCUCUGUUCAUGGCGUUCUCGAAGCUCUUGGAGCAAGCCGGAGGCGUGGGCCUCUUCCAGACCCUGCAGGUGCUCACCUUCAUCCUCCCCUGCCUCAUGAUACCUUCCCAGAUGCUCCUGGAGAACUUCUCAGCCGCCAUCCCAGGCCACCGAUGCUGGACACACAUGCUGGACAAUGGCUCUGCGGUUUCCACAAACAUGACCCCCAAGGCCCUUCUGACCAUCUCCAUCCCGCCAGGCCCCAACCAGGGGCCCCACCAGUGCCGCCGCUUCCGCCAGCCACAGUGGCAGCUCUUGGACCCCAAUGCCACGGCCACCAGCUGGAGCGAAGCUGACACGGAGCCGUGUGUGGACGGCUGGGUCUAUGACCGCAGCGUCUUCACCUCCACCAUCGUGGCCAAGUGGGACCUGGUGUGCAGCUCCCAGGGCUUGAAGCCCCUAAGCCAGUCCAUCUUCAUGUCCGGGAUCCUGGUGGGCUCCUUUAUCUGGGGCCUCCUCUCCUACCGGUUUGGGAGGAAGCCGAUGCUGAGCUGGUGCUGCCUGCAGUUGGCCGUGGCGGGCACCAGCACCAUCUUCGCCCCAACAUUCGUCAUCUACUGCGGCCUGCGGUUCGUGGCCGCUUUUGGGAUGGCCGGCAUCUUUCUGAGUUCACUGACACUGAUGGUGGAGUGGACCACGACCAGCAGGAGGGCGGUCACCAUGACGGUGGUGGGAUGUGCCUUCAGCGCAGGCCAGGCGGCGCUGGGCGGCCUGGCCUUUGCCCUGCGGGACUGGAGGACUCUCCAGCUGGCAGCAUCAGUGCCCUUCUUUGCCAUCUCCCUGAUAUCCUGGUGGCUGCCAGAAUCCGCCCGGUGGCUGAUUAUUAAGGGCAAACCAGACCAAGCACUUCAGGAGCUCAGAAAGGUGGCCAGGAUAAAUGGCCACAAGGAGGCCAAGAACCUGACCAUAGAGGUGCUGAUGUCCAGCGUGAAGGAGGAGGUGGCCUCUGCAAAGGAGCCGCGGUCGGUGCUGGACCUGUUCUGCGUGCCCGUGCUCCGCUGGAGGAGCUGCGCCAUGCUGGUGGUGAAUUUCUCUCUAUUGAUCUCCUACUAUGGGCUGGUCUUCGACCUGCAGAGCCUGGGCCGUGACAUCUUCCUCCUCCAGGCCCUCUUCGGGGCCGUGGACUUCCUGGGCCGGGCCACCACUGCCCUCUUGCUCAGUUUCCUUGGCCGCCGCACCAUCCAGGCGGGUUCCCAGGCCAUGGCCGGCCUCGCCAUUCUAGCCAACAUGCUGGUGCCGCAAGAUUUGCAGACCCUGCGUGUGGUCUUUGCUGUGCUGGGAAAGGGAUGUUUUGGGAUAAGCCUAACCUGCCUCACCAUCUACAAGGCUGAACUCUUUCCAACGCCAGUGCGGAUGACAGCAGAUGGCAUUCUGCAUACAGUGGGCCGGCUGGGGGCUAUGAUGGGUCCCCUGAUCCUGAUGAGCCGCCAAGCCCUGCCCCUGCUGCCUCCUCUCCUCUAUGGCGUUAUCUCCAUUGCUUCCAGCCUGGUUGUGCUGUUCUUCCUCCCGGAGACCCAGGGACUUCCGCUCCCUGACACUAUCCAGGACCUGGAGAGCCAGAAAUCAACAGCAGCCCAGGGCAACCGGCAAGAGGCCGUCACUGUGGAAAGUACCUCGCUCUAGAAAUUGUGCCUGCAUGGAGCCCCUUUAGUCAAAGACUCCUGGAAAGGAGUUGCCUCUUCUCCAAUCAGAGCGUGGAGGCGAGUUGGGCGACUUCAAGGGCCUGGCAUGGCAGAGGCCAGGCAGCCGUGGCCGAGUGGACAGCGUGGCCGUCUGCUGUGGCUGAAGGCAGCUUCCACAGCUCACUCCUCUUCUCCCUGCCCUGAUCAGAUUCCCCACCUUACCCGGGCCCUACAGGAGCCUGUGCAGAUGGCCAUGCCCAACCAAUAACGAGACGGUUCCCCUCCCUUUCCCUGCCAGGCUCAUGUCUUUACACCUUCACUCAGCCACGCCAACCAGAGACUGGGUUCCAAUCUCACCCCACCACAUACAGAGCCCUCAUCUGUGAAAUGAGAAUGAUCACGUGACCCACCCCCCAGGGCAGGUAUCAGGGUGAACUGAUCUUAGCACCGGCCAAAUAAAUGGAACCUGCUGAGAGAGCUGCCAGAUACAGGUGUCCAGGUUGUGCACUGGCCCGAGGCACGCAGCCAAGGAGGCGUGUGGGGUCUGAAACUCAGCCCCGGCUACACUGGCCCCACCACCCACCCUAGCAAAGGCUGUGUCCUCUCCAAAAAAAGGAGCUGUUUUAAUCACUUUUCAUUUACUCAUCAGUGAGGGAGGGCUUCCAGCCCUAUGGUUACGAAGACGGCCAAACACACCACCAAACACCAGACAGAGGAGGCUGGCAGCAGGUUACCACACACGUGCGCAGAGCCCACGAAGAUGACGCUGCACUGAGGCAUGGGGCGGGGUGCACUGAGGAUCCGAGCGAGCAGCCAGGGCUGCAGGAAGGCAGCUUUGGAGCACAAAGGGGGUGGGGCAACUCCUGGCUUCUGCGGGAAGGUGUAAUCAGCUUGUUUCAUCAUGCUGCAGGCUGGCGAGAAACGGAGCCUUACAAGCGUAGGGAUAAGAGGAACCCCUCUUGGUCCCCUCGAUGAGGGUUGUUGGGCCGGGGAGCCUCAUCCACAGGGCGGAGUGAAAGGGGAGAAGGGGAGCUCACAGGCAGGCCUGCCAAGGCCUUCUGGCUUUGCCAGAUGUCAAGGGCAGCACCUAAUACUGAACCUUAACUUUCGGCUUUCAACCAAACGGCACCCUUUUGCUGUUUGUUUUCUGGAGGGGACACCUUUUCUUGAUUCAUGCCCAGACCUCCCUUGUCCAGGCCAUGAAAACUCUGGGAUGGUCGAGGCCGGCUGCCCAUCUCAGAUGGGCAAGGAAGCAAAAGUGCAGAGUGGUGGAGGGGCCAGCUUGCAGAAACACGGCCGAACCCGGCCCUGAUCCUAGCCCAGGGCUCUUUCCAGCACAGGAGGCUCCUAGCCCUCGUCUCCAACCCUCCAUGCCACUGAUAUCUGUGGCCCUGCCACAAAGUUACCCUCAUGCCCUUCCCUGGAGACCCCACUCUGGGCCACCUCAAUCUCAGGCCCCUCAACUCACCUCUUUCACCCUGUGUACACUGGGUCAAUCACUCCUGCCUCCUCACAGCUCCCAAAUCCACCUACUUCCCUUCACUCUGGCUACACCCUGGUUCACACCACGGUUGUAGCUCCAAACUGGUCCCUGAUGUCUACAUUGCACUCUGCACAACAGCCACCAUGCUUAUUAAGAAACGCAAUCCAAACCAAAUCCCUCCCUGCUGAAAGCCCUCCAGUGGCUCACAAUAAGGAUCACACUUCUCCCCCUGCCUGGUCAGGCAGCCAUGGGACCCCAGCCUUUCCUCCCACUUCGGUAAAUUUUAAAGGAUUCGGAUCAUACAAAGAAUGUUCUUGAACCAGCAUGGAAUUAAAUUAGAAAUCAAUUAUG